GGAUUGCAGGCAUGAGUCACCACGCCUGGCCCAAACACAACUAUUUUUUAGUAUAUCUAAAAUAGAGCAUUUUUAGACAUGCUGAGAGUGAGAGUGCUAACUACAUAUAUGCCUUCAUGAAGGAACUAUCAAAGGAUAUACCUUCAUCAAGAAUGAUUUGAACCUAGGAGGAAGUUGUGGAUGCAAGAAACAAAAAAUGUCCCUGGCUGCUUAUUGCGUCAUCUGUUGCAGAAGAAUAGGAACCUCUACUUCCCCACCAAAAAGUGGCACACACUGGAGAGAUAUCAGAAAUAUAAUAAAGUUUACUGGAUCACUUAUUUUAGGAGGUUCUUUAUUUCUUACAUAUGAAGUUCUGGCCCUGAAGAAGGCUGUGACAUUAGAUACUCAAGUGGUAGAACGAGAAAAAAUGAAGUCAUAUAUAUAUGUGCACACAGUUUCUUUAGACAAAGGAGAAAAUCAUGGUAUUGCCUGGCAGGCAAGAAAAGAACUUCACAAAGCAGUAAGAAAAGUAUUGGCAACAUCAGCCAAGAUACUGCGGAAUCCAUUUGCUGAUCCUUUUAGUACAGUUGAUAUAGAAGAUCAUGAGUGUGCUGUGUGGCUGCUCCUACGGAAGAGCAAGUCAGAUGACAAAACCACGCGACUCGAGGCUGUGCGGGAAAUGUCGGAGACCCAUCACUGGCAUGAUUACCAGUAUAGGAUAAUUGCUCAAGCCUGUGAUCCGAAAACUCUUAUUGGUUUGGCACGAAGCGAAGAGAGUGAUCUUCGCUUUUUUCUCCUACCACCUCCUUUGCCAUCUUUAAAAGAAGAUUCUUCCACUGAAGAAGAGCUCAGACAGUUGCUGGCUUCCUUACCUCAAACAGAGCUAGAUGAGUGUAUCCAGUAUUUUACAUCUUUGGCUCUUAGUGAAAGCAGUCAGAGUCUAGCUGCUCAGAAGGGUGGUUUAUGGUGUUUUGGAGGAAAUGGACUUCCUUAUGCUGAAAGUUUUGGAGAAGUUCCUUCAGCAACAGUGGAAAUGUUCUGUUUAGAAGCUAUAGUAAAACAUUCUGAGAUAUCCACACAUUGUGAUAAAAUCGAAGCAAAUGGAGGCCUGCAGCUACUUCAGAGGCUGUACCGACUUCACAAGGACUGCCCUAAAGUACAGAGAAAUAUAAUGCGUGUCAUUGGAAAUAUGGCUUUGAAUGAACAUCUUCAUUCUUCUAUAGUUCGCUCAGGCUGGGUUUCCAUCAUGGCAGAAGCAAUGAAAUCUCCCCACAUUAUGGAGUCCUCACACGCUGCCAGAAUCCUGGCAAAUCUAGACCGAGAAACUGUGCAAGAAAAAUAUCAGGAUGGCGUAUAUGUGCUGCAUCCCCAAUAUCGAACAAGUCAGCCCAUUAAAGCAGAUGUCCUUUUUAUUCAUGGCCUUAUGGGAGCAGCAUUCAAAACAUGGCGCCAGCAGGACAGUGAGCAGGCUGUAAUUGAAAAACCUAUGGAGGAUGAAGACAGAUAUACGACGUGCUGGCCCAAGACAUGGUUAGCAAAAGACUGUCCUGCUCUCCGAAUUAUAUCUGUGGAGUAUGACACCAGCCUCAGCGACUGGAGAGCAAGGUGCCCUAUGGAAAGAAAGUCCAUUGCAUUCAGAAGCAACGAACUUCUUAGGAAGCUCAGAGCUGCUGGUGUUGGGGAUAGGCCAGUGGUUUGGAUAUCACAUAGCAUGGGAGGUCUUCUUGUCAAAAAGAUGCUGUUGGAAGCCUCUACGAAGCCAGAAAUGAGUACUGUUAUCAACAAUACCAGAGGAAUAAUUUUUUAUAGUGUCCCUCAUCAUGGAUCACGUUUGGCUGAAUACUCUGUUAAUAUUCGCUAUCUUCUCUUCCCCUCGUUGGAAGUCAAAGAACUCAGCAAGGAUUCUCCUGCACUUAAAACACUACAAGAUGACUUUCUGGAGUUUGCUAAAGACAAAAACUUCCAGGUGCUGAAUUUUGUGGAAACACUACCAACCUACAUUGGCAGCAUGAUUAAGCUCCAUGUGGUACCUGUGGAAUCAGCAGAUUUAGGCAUUGGAGAUCUAAUUCCUGUGGAUGUUAACCAUUUGAACAUUUGUAAGCCAAAGAAAAAGGAUGCUUUUUUGUACCAGCGUACUUUACAAUUCAUUCGUGAAGCUUUAGCCAAAGACCUUGAAAACUAACAGUUGUGCUCUUCCAGUUUUCAUAUGUGAAUUCAGUGCAAGAAACUUGGUGUUCUGUUUCUUCUUUUAAGCUCUAUGCAAUCAUGCAAACAUAGUGAUCAUAGCGUCAACAUGGUCUGGAGUGUGUUGCAGACUACAGAACAUUGUUCUCCCUUCAAGCGCUGUAAAGCACCAACCCGGAAGUGGCAGGCACAGAAGGAAGGGCUGGAUUGGGCCCCUUUGGUGUAAAGAAGUCCCUGUGUGCUGCUUUAUGGUUCGCAGUGUUGGGCUUGGUGACUGGAGCAAAGCUGCUGUGAGAGAGUGUCCUUUCCCAUCUGUGACUUUCCUGGUGCAUCCAGGAGGGGCACGGCAGGUUCUGAGGUAACUCAACUUACCAUAAAAAUGCCAUUAAGAGAGUACCUAAAAUGGAGAGAAGAAUGAACUAGAACAUUCAAGACUCUUUUACUUCUGGGUAUUGAUUUGCUGUACAUUUUUAAAGUUUGAGUUUUUAGCUCAGUUCUACCUUUUAUCUGACACAUUAUUACUAGUGUUAACUUUGUUAGACUUAUUGUCAUGUCUGGGUCAGUUCCUUGUAUCUAUUUUCGUAUUCCUGAGAACAAAUCUUUUUCUUAGAAAAAUUCUAGCUUAUAAUAAUUCUUUUCAGACUGUAGCUGCCUAUGCUUGGAAUUUGUCCUAGAUAAGGAUAAAGUAGCUAAUCCAUUAUUGAUCACAGUAUGAAGUAAAACUAUUCUAAGCCAUUAUAUGAAUUAGCAAUUCUUAGUAUCAAGAUUCUCAGAUUCUCUUUGGCUAAAUAAACCUUUCUUCUUCCUUGCUCAUUUGCAAGUGGUAUUAAUUGACCUCUAUAGCAUGUGAGUAGUAGAUAAUCAUGUCGAUGACCUUUUUUUCUUUAGAGUAACAGCAUUAUUGAGAUAUAAUUUACAUACCAUAAGAUUCACCCUUUUAAAUUAUACAAUUCAUUUUUGUUUUGUUUUGUUUGUUUAGAGACAGGGUCUGACUCUGUUGCCCAAGCUGGAGUGCAGUGGCAUGAUCAUAGCUCAUUGUAACCUCAAACUCCUGGGCUCAAGAGAUCCUUUUGCUUCAGCCUCCCAAGCAGCUAGGACUACAGGCACAUGCCACCACACUUGGGUAAUUAAAAAAUAAAUAAAUACUUUUUUGUAGAGACAGGGUCUCACUGUGUUGCCCAGGUCUCAAACUCCCGAUCUCAAGCCACCCUCCCAAAAUGCUGUGAUUAUAGGCCAGAGCCAUUGUUCCCAGGCUCAAUUCAUUGGUUUUUAGUAUAGUUCACUGAGUUGUGCAACAUCAUUGCUAUUUAAUUUCAGGCUAUUUCAUCAUCCCCAAAAGAACCCCAUACCCAUGAGCAGUCAGUUCCCACCUCUGCUUUCCCAAGCCUGCGGUAAACACUAAUCUGUUUUCUGUCUCUAUGGAUUUGGGAAUUUUAUGUAAAUGGAAUCAUACAAUAUGUGGCCCUCUCUGCCUUCUUCCUUCUAUUAGCAUGUUUUCAAGGUUCAUUCAUGAUAUAGCAUGUAUCAGUACUACUUCAUUUCUUUUUAUGGCCGAAAUUACUCCAUUGUAUGAUAUGCCAUGUUUCUUUAUCCAUUCAUCAGCUGAUGGACAUCUAGGUUCUGUUCAUUUUUGUCUAUGAUAAAUAAUGCUACCAUGAUCAUUUGUGUACAAAUUUAUGUGUGGAUAGAUGUUUUUGAUUCUCUUGGGUGGAAUUGCUGGUCAAAUGGUAAGUCUAUGUUUAAAUUUUGAAGAUGGUGAACUUUUGUAGAAUGAGAUAGUCGAAGCUAAAACUGGAGUAUGGCAUCUGAAGGUAAAUGGCUCAUCAAUAAACUCGAUAUCAACAA